CACAGUUGAUUGUCAGUGUGUAAGCCACAGAUUCUGAAGGUUAAGAGCUUCUGCCUUUUGUGUGGUGGGAACUUGAAGAAGGGUAGAGGACUAACUGGUCUGGGAUGAAUCCUUGGAGGAGGUGGUACUUAAUUCUGGGAUGAGUGGGGUUUGCCUGUGGGACUGCAGAAUACCUUCCAGGCAAGGAGAAGGACCCCAGAGUGAGUAAGCUGUGUCCUGAGAGAAGGGAAGGGGAAAUGAGUCCUUAAAGUAGAGAAAAACUUUUCUAAGUUGGAAAUCAAAGCAGAUGCAACAUGCUCCGCCUACACUGUGCAGCAGGGAAGGUACUGGCUUCUUUAUGCCCUCUGGGUCUGCUGGGUUGCCAUGGUGAGCCCAGCUCACACACAGUAGGUGACUCAGGCCACCUGCCCAUUUCCCUAAAGCGGCUAGGGCCCAGGCACACCUCUGAGGCUCUGCUAGUGGGGAAGCAACCACCUUUGAGGCAGCAGACGCAAGAGAAAGCCUCUGAAGGUGGACAGGCUUUGAGGAUGCAGCUAGGAAGCCCUGACUGGCCUCUGCUGUUUCCUGGACUGAAGGUCCCUGUUCUCUGUUCUCACUCUGCUUCUAGGAAUGAAAGUAUAGAAUAUUCUAAUUCUAGAAUGUUAGAGAUGGAAAAAUCCUUAUCAUAGCUUGUAACCCCCAGGCCCAAAGGGAAAUGGAGAUGUUUUGAUCAAGUUCUCUGUUUUUCCAGUUGAGGCCCAGAGAGGAUUGGCCCCAGGCCACUCGUGAAUUAAUGGCAGAGUCAGUCUUCUUCCCUGCUCUGUUAACUAACUCAGGAGUCCCUAGGCAGUAAGACCUGGACAGUGGACCGAGAGGAGGGGCUGUGGUUUUUGGCUUGGAUAUUGGUAGCAUUGGCAAACCUCAGUUCUUCCAGUGGGCCCUUUAAGCCUAAAGAAGGGCAGCUUCCUCCUGGGGUAUCUAUUAGGGAGCUGUCCUUGGCAGAGAAACCAUUGGUCCUUACACUGGUCCUUACAGGGGAGCCAAGUACAGGUCUUGGGACCUCUGAGACAGCCCAGAGGCUUCUGCCUUCACCCAUUGAAUCCCUCAGGUCGUGUAGUCCAUCACAAGCCAAUGUUGAACUUGGGUGCUGUGCUUUUUAUAGCAUCUUUGCCAUCAAGCCAGGGAAUAAGAUCUUAUCUCCCCGGUGGCCAGGACCCACAGGAAUCUGGAUGCUGUACCAGGCCUGUUCCUCCAUACAGCUGUGGCAUUUGCUCGAUCCCCAGCCUGGAGCACUGCCCAUAGACUGCCUCGCGCCGGUGCUCUCCUUCAGGCCCUAGAUCAAACGUCAUCUCUUCAGAGAGGCCUCCCUGACUGUCCAGUCUAACGGGCAGCACACGCCCCACCAGCUGCCUCUACCCCCAUGUCAGACACUAUUCUGGAUCUGAGGACACAGCCAGGAACAAGACAGAAGAGGCUCCUGAUGUCAGGGGGCUCCCAUGCCAGCAUGGAGCAUUGGAUGUGGACAAAGCAGUGUCAGGUAGUGAUAAUUCUGGGGUAACCACAGUUCUGACUUGGAUCAUCAUCAGUUGAUCUUACCUGUUCUUGAACUUCAUCUGAAUGGAAUCAUAGCUUAACUUUUUAAAUUAAAUCGGAUCUUUUGAAAGAGUUUCCUUAUCGGCAUCAAGAGAACAGCUUCAAGAGGGGAGAGUCUGGGAUGGACCCUGAAACCAGUCACUUGCGGCCGUUCACCCUGGCCGGGCAGAUUUCCUUCUAGGUGGAACCCAGGAUCUGGCCAGAACCCAGGGUGUAAAUCUUGGCUCUGUUGCUCCCUGUCUGGACCUGAUGUUCCCAGAGGGUGAGACCCUUUCUCUCCAACAUAGUAGGACCCCCUGAAAUGUGGAUUGAAACAAGCAAGAAAUAGAAGUGCUGUUUGGAAGAAUGAUGGGGAAAAACACAGAGAGAGACUGAUUGCCCGGGUAUGGGGAAGGAUGCUUGCCCAGGUUUCCAUGUGAUCCCCACUAUCUCAAGCAUCGUCCCGGAGAGCUGCCUGCUGAUCGUGGUGGGGCUGCUGGUGGGGGGCCUGAUCAAGGGUGUAGGCGAGACACCCCCCUUCCUGCAGUCCGACGUCUUCUUCCUCUUCCUGCUGCCGCCCAUCAUCCUGGAUGCGGGCUACUUCCUGCCACUGCGGCAGUUCACAGAAAACCUGGGCACCAUCCUGAUCUUUGCCGUGGUGGGCACGCUGUGGAACGCCUUCUUCCUGGGCGGCCUCAUGUACGCCGUGUGCCUGGUGGGCGGUGAGCAGAUCAACAACAUCGGCCUCCUGGACAACCUGCUCUUCGGCAGCAUCAUCUCGGCCGUGGACCCCGUGGCGGUUCUGGCUGUCUUUGAGGAAAUUCACAUCAAUGAGCUGCUGCACAUCCUUGUUUUUGGGGAGUCCUUGCUCAAUGACGCCGUCACUGUGGUCCUGUAUCACCUCUUUGAGGAGUUUGCCAACUACGAACACGUGGGCAUCGUGGACAUCUUCCUCGGCUUCCUGAGCUUCUUCGUGGUGGCCCUGGGCGGGGUGCUUGUGGGCGUGGUCUACGGGGUCAUCGCAGCCUUCACCUCCCGAUUUACCUCCCACAUCCGGGUCAUCGAGCCGCUCUUCGUCUUCCUCUACAGCUACAUGGCCUACUUGUCAGCCGAGCUCUUCCACCUGUCAGGCAUCAUGGCGCUCAUAGCCUCAGGAGUGGUGAUGCGCCCCUAUGUGGAGGCCAACAUCUCCCACAAGUCCCACACCACCAUCAAAUACUUCCUGAAGAUGUGGAGCAGCGUCAGCGAGACCCUCAUCUUCAUCUUCCUCGGCGUCUCCACGGUGGCCGGCUCCCACCACUGGAACUGGACCUUCGUCAUCAGCACCCUGCUCUUCUGCCUCAUCGCCCGCGUGCUGGGGGUGCUGGGCCUGACCUGGUUCAUCAACAAGUUCCGUAUCGUGAAGCUGACCCCCAAGGACCAGUUCAUCAUCGCCUAUGGGGGCCUGCGAGGGGCCAUCGCCUUCUCUCUGGGCUACCUCCUGGACAAGAAGCACUUCCCCAUGUGUGACCUGUUCCUCACUGCCAUCAUCACUGUCAUCUUCUUCACCGUCUUUGUGCAGGGCAUGACCAUUCGGCCCCUGGUAGACCUGUUGGCUGUGAAGAAAAAGCAAGAGACGAAGCGCUCCAUCAACGAAGAGAUCCACACACAGUUCCUGGACCACCUUCUGACAGGCAUCGAAGACAUCUGUGGCCACUACGGUCACCACCACUGGAAGGACAAGCUCAACCGGUUUAAUAAGAAAUAUGUGAAGAAGUGUCUGAUAGCUGGCGAGCGCUCCAAGGAGCCCCAGCUCAUUGCCUUCUACCACAAGAUGGAGAUGAAGCAGGCCAUCGAGCUGGUGGAGAGCGGGGGCAUGGGCAAGAUCCCCUCUGCCGUCUCCACCGUCUCCAUGCAGAACAUCCACCCCAAGUCCCUGCCUUCCGAGCGCAUCCUGCCAGCACUGUCCAAGGACAAGGAGGAGGAGAUCCGCAAAAUCCUGAGGAACAACUUGCAGAAGACCAGGCAGCGGCUGCGGUCCUACAACAGACACACGCUGGUGGCAGACCCCUACGAGGAAGCCUGGAACCAGAUGCUGCUCCGGAGGCAGAAGGCCCGGCAGCUGGAGCAGAAGAUCAACAACUACCUGACGGUGCCAGCCCACAAGCUGGACUCACCCACCAUGUCUCGGGCCCGCAUCGGCUCAGACCCACUGGCCUAUGAGCCGAAGGAGGACCUGCCUGUCAUCACCAUCGACCCGGCUUCCCCGCAGUCACCCGAGUCUGUGGACCUGGUGAAUGAAGAGCUGAAGGGCAAAGUCUUAGGGUUGAGCCGGGAUCCUGCAAAGGUGGCUGAGGAGGACGAGGACGACGAUGGGGGCAUCAUGAUGCGGAGCAAGGAGACUUCGUCCCCAGGAACCGACGAUGUCUUCACCCCCGCGCCCAGUGACAGCCCCAGCUCCCAGAGGAUACAGCGCUGCCUCAGUGACCCAGGCCCACACCCUGAGCCUGGGGAGGGAGAACCGUUCUUCCCCAAGGGGCAGUAACACCAGGGCCAGCAGGCAGCGCCUGUCCCCUCACAGACUCUUCCACCAGAGCAGGGGCUGCUGGGGGCUCCCCUUGCCCUUCCUGACCCGGAUUGGCCCUGCCCCUCCCCCUACCGCAUGGCAGCUGGGCCCACAGCCCCCACCCCAGCACAGCUCCUCCCCUGCCGCCUCCCGGGAAGCAUCCUCCCCACCAGAGCUGCCUCCCCAAUCCAUUUGGCAGAACUGCUGGGGCUGGUGAGGCCGGCCCUGCCCCUCCCUAGAUCCAGGCUUCUCCCGGACCUGGACUAGGGCCUCGGAGGCUCCUCCCUCUGCCUCAUCCUCCUCCUCAUUCAGACCAAUCUUAGUUUCUAACCAAAGAGUCUCUGGCUCAGCUGUGGUCCCACCCAGGAAGGGAGGGAGCUGAGGCCUCCCUUGAGUAGGCCCUGCUUUAUCAGGGGACAAACCAGGGGUACCAGGCACAUGGCUGGGGGAGGGACUGCUGACCCACCAAGGUCUCACACUCCUCCUGCCAGCUCUGUCACCCUGGCCACCACCCAACCUGUCCUUACUCAGAGCUGCGGGCUGAGGGCAUCUCUGAGUGUCUCUGCCUGGAGCAGGGGUGGUUUCUACGGUGACAGUGACGUGACUCAGAGCUUUUCGAACUGUGCUCCCACGGGGACCACUGGGCCCCUCAGGGGAAGCUGCUAGGGGAAGGACUGGCCGUGGCUCCAGAAUGUGCUGCCUUUUUAAGUUUUGUUUGUUCACACUCCUAUAUAUGAUUGUUUGCACAGAGGGCGCUCCUGUUUUUAAAACAUUUUGAAAACCCCUGGCUGAACAGUGCUCUGCCUCUAACUCCCUCCUCACACUCCAGAAUUACCCUUCCUCAUCUGUGCCUGUCUGUCCAACCCCUCCCCCACGUCUCUCUGCCUGCUGGGCUCUUAACUGUUGCUCGAAGACUGUGACAUCAGAAGUAACUCCCACUCCUAAUCAAGAGUCUCUCCAGCCUCACAGAUGCUGGCCUCUUGGCACCUGCCUAGCUCUUGGGCCUGACCUCCAGUCCUGCUGGCCUGCUCUUACUUCCCCCACCCUGGGUUUGGCCCCUGGAACCUUUCCCUUGUGUGUACCACACCCUGCCUGCUGUGGAGCCCAUUGUGGAGGCGGUGGGGGGGAGAAGGCCUCCCCUGAGGAUCCCCUGUCCCCUGGGGCUGGUGGAUUGGGCAGAAUCCUGGGCCCCCAGAGACCUUUGCCCACACACACUCCUUCCCCUUGUCCCUGGGGCACUCCCCCAGGAUUGUGCAAUAGUCAGAGUGUCCCUUUUUGCAGGGGACUGGGCCAUGGGUCCUCGGCCCAUCUGUCCAUCCUCCUCUCCAUGCAAGUGCUGUUUGGGCAGGAGUCACCAUGCAAGGGUGACAUCGACAACCACGUACCAAGCCACCGCAGCUGCUGCCACUCUGCUGCCUGUACAGAAGAAACUGAAUCUUUUUCAUAUUCUAAUAAAUCAAUGUGAGUUUUUAAUAGA